GUGGCGCGCGCGCGCGCGCCGCCAGCGGUAGCGGACCUUGAGUGGCAGGGGGUGGGGGGGGCGCCCUCGGAGCCGGGCGGAGGGGAGGGGGGAAAGAGGAGCGCAGGGUGAGAGUGAGCCGCAGGCUUCGGGAGGCGAGGGGGCGGGGGGAGCAGCGCCGAGGCCGCCGCCUCCGCCUCCGCCGCCUAGGACUAGGGGGUGGGGGACGGACAAGCCCCGAUGCCGGGGGAGACGGAAGAGCCGAGACCCCCGGAGCAGCAGGACCAGGAAGGGGGAGAGGCGGCCAAGGCGGCUCCGGAGGAGCCCCAACAACGGCCCCCUGAGGCGGUCGCGGCGGCGCCUGCAGGGACCACUAGCAGCCGCGUGCUGAGGGGAGGUCGGGACCGAGGCCGGGCCGCUGCGGCCGCCGCCGCCGCAGCUGUGUCCCGCCGGAGGAAGGCCGAGUAUCCCCGCCGGCGGAGGAGCAGCCCCAGCGCCAGGCCUCCCGACGUCCCCGGGCAGCAGCCCCAGGCCGCGAAGUCCCCGUCUCCAGUUCAGGGCAAGAAGAGUCCGCGACUCCUAUGCAUAGAAAAAGUAACAACUGAUAAAGAUCCCAAGGAAGAAAAAGAGGAAGAAGACGAUUCUGCCCUCCCUCAGGAAGUUUCCAUUGCUGCAUCUAGACCUAGCCGGGGCUGGCGUAGUAGUAGGACAUCUGUUUCUCGCCAUCGUGAUACAGAGAACACCCGAAGCUCUCGGUCCAAGACCGGUUCAUUGCAGCUCAUUUGCAAGUCAGAACCAAAUACAGACCAACUUGAUUAUGAUGUUGGAGAAGAGCAUCAGUCUCCAGGUGGCAUUAGUAGUGAAGAGGAAGAGGAGGAGGAAGAAGAGAUGUUAAUCAGUGAAGAGGAGAUACCAUUCAAAGAUGAUCCAAGAGAUGAGACCUACAAACCCCACUUAGAAAGGGAAACCCCAAAGCCACGGAGAAAAUCAGGGAAGGUAAAAGAAGAGAAGGAGAAGAAGGAAAUUAAAGUGGAAGUAGAGGUGGAGGUGAAAGAAGAGGAGAAUGAAAUUAGAGAGGAUGAGGAACCUCCAAGGAAGAGAGGAAGAAGACGAAAAGAUGACAAAAGUCCACGUUUACCCAAAAGGAGAAAAAAGCCUCCAAUCCAGUAUGUCCGUUGUGAGAUGGAAGGAUGUGGAACUGUCCUUGCCCAUCCUCGCUAUUUGCAGCACCACAUUAAAUACCAGCAUUUGCUGAAGAAGAAAUAUGUAUGUCCCCAUCCCUCCUGUGGACGACUCUUCAGGCUUCAGAAGCAACUUCUGCGACAUGCCAAACAUCAUACAGAUCAAAGGGAUUAUAUCUGUGAAUAUUGUGCUCGGGCCUUCAAGAGUUCCCACAAUCUGGCAGUGCACCGGAUGAUUCACACUGGCGAGAAGCCAUUACAAUGUGAGAUCUGUGGAUUUACUUGUCGACAAAAGGCAUCUCUUAAUUGGCACAUGAAGAAACAUGAUGCAGACUCCUUCUACCAGUUUUCUUGCAAUAUCUGUGGCAAAAAAUUUGAGAAGAAGGACAGCGUAGUGGCACACAAGGCAAAAAGCCACCCUGAGGUGCUGAUUGCAGAAGCUCUGGCUGCCAAUGCAGGCGCCCUCAUCACCAGCACAGAUAUCUUGGGCACUAACCCAGAGUCCCUGACGCAGCCUUCAGAUGGUCAGGGUCUUCCUCUUCUUCCUGAGCCCUUGGGAAACUCAACCUCUGGAGAGUGCCUACUGUUAGAAGCUGAAGGGAUGUCAAAGUCAUACUGCAGUGGGACGGAACGGGUGAGCCUGAUGGCUGAUGGGAAGAUCUUUGUGGGAAGCGGCAGCAGUGGAGGCACUGAAGGGCUGGUUAUGAACUCAGAUAUACUCGGUGCUACCACAGAGGUUCUGAUUGAAGAUUCAGACUCUGCCGGACCUUAGUGGACAGGAAGACUUGGGGCAUGGGACAGCUCAGACUUUGUAUUUAAAAGUUAAAAAGGACAAAAAAAAAAUCUAAAGCAUUUAAAAUCUAGUGAAAUAACUGAAGGGCCUGCUCUUUCCAUUGUGGAUCACAGCACACACAUACAUACACCCUCCACCUCCCCAUCCCCUGUUCUCCCUCUGUUGCUCCCCUUAUAAAAUUGAUGUUGUCUUUACCAGAAAGGUAGACAAAAAAGAAGCAGCAGCAGCUCUUAAAGUGAGGGUUAUUCUCAUACUCGGUUCCAGCCAUCAGCAGACUUCCUGCUCAUCGGCAGAUCCCCCUUUCCAACCUGUAACUCUGAUGUGCUCUGGAUCAGCUUUUAACUUUUAAUCAUAUAUUACUGUCUUCUAAAUCCCUUCUCCUCCUCUACUGCUGCCCUAUGGUUCUGGCUCCUACCCCCUGCGGCACACUUAUCUUCAAAUACCAUAGAAUUCUAAUCUCUGGAGGCUGGCAGCUUGACUUGGCACUUUAGGGCCCCUUAGCAGGGUGAGCUGUUAAAACAGCACACAUCUCUCAUCCCCUCUUCCUUUAUUCCCCCCUGGGUUUCAGAAAGGAAGGAUAUAUGGGGACCACCUCCCCCUUCUUUGAUCCCAGCAUCUCAGUCCCCCUCCCAACCCUCCAUAUGGCUCUCAAUGGUGCUCACUUGCUUGGAAGCAGGCUCCCAAUAGGGAGGGGGCUGCCCUCUACAGUCUCUUUGACUGUAAGACAGGGCUCUGUAUCAGUGAGACGAUGAGAAAAGUCCCAGGCUAAUGGCAGAAAUUUGCACUUUGAACAUGUGUGUUUUUGUGUUGUGGAACCUGAGAUUCCUUAUUUAUUAACAGGAAGUCUGAUUUUUUUUUUUUGGAGUCUUUGUUGCUAUAUUUUGUGGGGCUGGGAGAGAGAGAUUAGAUUAUUUUGACAUGGGAUCCCUUCCAUAACAGGUACUUUGAAGGCAAGACAUAGGGUUGAAGAAGCACAGCCAGCCUCUGAAAUCAUAGCUCUCCAGUGGCUUUUAAAGAAAGCUGGUCCUCAGCACUAACAAAAUCACUACAAUAGCCUAGUGCUUUUUUGGAAGCCUUUUUAGGGAAGAAUGUUAGGUUCAUGGUAACUAGUAUGCUCUUUGAGAUUUUUACAGUGUUGAAACUUAAGAAUUUUGAGAGGGUGAGGAGGGUUGUUCAGAAUCUAAAUUACAGAUAGAUGAUUGUUUCUUGUGAAUUUGUUUCUUUUCCUUUUUUUUUGUCCCUACCAUUUCCUUACAUUUCCCUUGGGGCCCAUCUCUGGCUCCUUGCUUUUUGUUUCUUGCUUUGCUUUAUCAGUUCAUUCCAGCUCCCUGUUAGUGAAGGACACUGCUGUUAGUGAAGGAACAAAGUCUAUGAGUCCUAAAAUUUUAAGUCAAAGAAAACUGCUCUGUUUCCCCUUUAGUAACACUUCUGAAGAGGAAAAACUUCAAUAGCCAAAGUUAAUAAUCCUAUAUAAUAAUUGCUUUGGCUUUCACCUAAAAUUCUGGGCAUCACAAUUUCCUUGGGAUAGAGGUUGUGUUGGGGAAUAGAUUGCUUAUUGCUGUUCACUGGAGAGAAAAGGUAGUGUUUUUGUACAAGGUCAUACCGCCAGAAGCCCCAAAUCCUAUUUUGGCUCAUCUUCAGGUAAAGAGUAAUUCCUAUCCUGUGUGCCUCAGAAGCUAGAAUCGAAGGCUUACCCUAUUCAUUGUUUAUUGUCAGAAAUGCAUGAUGGCUCUUGGAAAGAAUGACGUUUUGCUGGAAAAAAAAAAAAGAACAGUUUGUGUUUCACAAACAUGGCUUAUCAAUUUUUUCAAAGAAUUCUUUUUUCCCAAAAAGAGGAGUAACAAAAUGUCAUUUCUGAAAGAGGCUUACUUUAUACCAACUAGUGUCAGCAUUUGGGAUGCCAGGGAACAGAGAGUGAGACACCUACAAUCACCAGUCUCAAAUGCGCUAUUGUUUCUUUUCAGAGUGUUGCAGAUUUGCCAUUUCUCCAUAAUAUGGGGAUAGAAAAUGGAAUAAAGAUAGAAGGGAUGUAGAAUAUGCUUUCCUGCCAACAUGGUUUGGAGUCGACUUUGGUAUAUUGACUAGAUUUGAAAAUACAAGAUUGAUUAGAUGAAUCUACAAAAAAGUUGUCCUCCUCUCAGGUCCCUUUUACACUUUUUGACUAACUAGCAUCUAUAUUCCACACUUAGCUUUUUUGUCACACUUAUCCUUUGUCUCCGUAAAUUUCAUUUGCAGUGGUUAGUCAUCAGAUAUUUUAGCCACCUACACAAAAGCAAACUGCAUUUUUAAAAAUCUUUCUGAGAUGGGAGAAAAUGUAUUCUCCUUUCCUAUACCGCUCUCCCAACAAAAAAACAACUAGUUAGUUCUACUAAUUAGAAACUUGCUGUACUUUUUCUUUUCUUUUAGGGGUCAAGGACCCUCUUUAUAGCUACCAUUUGCCUACAAUAAAUUAUUGCAGCAGUUUGCAAUACUAAAAUAUUUUUUAUAGACUUUAUAUUUUUCCUUUUGAUAAAGGGAUGCUGCAUAGUAGAGUUGGUGUAAUUAAACUAUCUCAGCCGUUUCCCUGCUUUCCCUUCUGCUCCAUAUGCCUCAUUGUCCUUCCAGGGAGCUCUUUUAAUCUUAAAGUUCUACAUUUCAUGCUCUUAGUCAAAUUCUGUUACCUUUUUAAUAACUCUUCCCACUGCAUAUUUCCAUCUUGAAUUGGUGGUUCUAAAUUCUGAAACUGUAGUUGAGAUACAGCUAUUUAAUAUUUCUGGGAGAUGUGCAUCCCUCUUCUUUGUGGUUGCCCAAGGUUGUUUUGCGUAACUGAGACUCCUUGAUAUGCUUCAGAGAAUUUAGGCAAACACUGGCCAUGGCCGUGGGAGUACUGGGAGUAAAAUAAAAAUAUCGAGGUAUAGACUAGCAUCCACAUAGAGCACUUGAACCUCCUUUGUACCUGUUUGGGGAAAAAGUAUAAUGAGUGUACUACCAAUCUAACUAAGAUUAUUAUAGUCUGGUUGUUUGAAAUACCAUUUUUUUCUCCUUUUGUGUUUUUCCCACUUUCCAAUGUACUCAAGAAAAUUGAACAAAUGUAAUGGAUCAAUUUAAAAUAUUUUAUUUCUUAAAAGCCUUUUUUGCCUGUUGUAAUGUGCAGGACCCUUCUCCUUUCAUGGGAGAGACAGGUAGUUACCUGAAUAUAGGUUGAAAAGGUUAUGUAAAAAGAAAUUAUAAUAAAAGGGAUACUUUGCUUUUCAAAUCUUUGUUUUCUCUUAUUCUAGGUAAGGCAUAUUAAAAAUAAAUAUGUAAAGAAGAAAAAUAAAAGUUGUCUUCAUGGAAGCAACUUGUCUUCCUUGGUUGUACUGAGUUACAGUUAUCCUAGGGGUGAAACAUGUGAUGCUGCUAAGCAAACCAAAUGCCCUCAGAACAGGUGUUAUGUGGGGCAUACUAUUGUUUGCUUUUGUUGAGAAUCAGGUGGUUAAUUUUUGACUGUUCUUGAUUUCUAAUGCUGAAAUGACAUGAUUCUGUUAUUCAGCAAACUUGGAAAUCUUGAUGUUUUGACAACUGCCUCCUAGGAAAACUGGCCAUAUGUUAAUUAACCUAGUAGAUGGAAAAUUAAGGAUUAUGUGAGGUUAAUUUUACCCUGAUAAUGACAAAACCUUGAUAGCAUUUAAUAUUAAUACUUCUUCUCAAAAUUGAAUGUUUAUAUCAAGUACUGAUUUUUAUUUUAAAAAAGAAAAAACUAUAAUCCUUCUGCCUUCCAAAAGCCAUGCUGUGAUAGCUGCCCAGGCUGCUCUGUUACAUCUCCCAUUUAUUGUUUACUUUUAUAAAUUUGCUUCUAAGAUGG